AGAGCUGCUGUGGCGGCGGCAACAUGGCGGACGUGAUAAAUGUCAGUGUGAACCUGGAGGCCUUUUCCCAGGCCAUUAGUGCCAUCCAGGCGCUGCGCUCCAGCGUGAGCAGGGUGUUCGACUGCCUGAAGGAUGGGAUGCGGAACAAGGAGACGCUGGAGGGCCGGGAGAAGGCCUUUAUUGCGCACUUCCAGGACAACUUACAUUCGGUCAACCGGGACCUCAAUGAGCUGGAACGUCUGAGCAAUCUGGUAGGCAAGCCAUCUGAGAACCAUCCUCUUCAUAACAGUGGGCUGUUAAGCCUGGAUCCUGUGCAGGACAAAACUCCUCUCUAUAGUCAACUCCUUCAAGCAUAUAAGUGGUCAAACAAGUUGCAGUACCAUGCAGGACUAGCAUCUGGCCUUUUAAAUCAGCAGUCAUUGAAGCGUUCCGCUAAUCAGAUGGGAGUAUCUGCCAAACGUAGACCAAAGGCUCAGCCCACAACUCUUGUCCUACCACCUCAAUAUGUUGAUGAUGUGAUCAGCCGCAUUGACAGGAUGUUUCCUGAAAUGUCCAUCCACUUAUCCAGACCCAAUGGAACAUCAGCAAUGCUUCUGGUGACCUUGGGAAAGGUGUUGAAAGUGAUCGUCGUCAUGCGGAGCCUGUUCAUUGAUCGAACAAUAGUAAAGGGAUAUAACGAGAAUGUCUACACAGAAGAUGGCAAGUUCUUCCUGUGUGUCAAGAGGUCUUUUGAUGUCUUGGUGUUUGCCCUGAGAACAGACGUGUCUGUGCUGAAGCAAUUGGUCAUCUGCAAGCUUGAUAUAUGGUCCAAAUCCAACUAUCAAGUAUUCCAGAAGGCCUGUUUUUUCCAAGUCUUGGAUGCUGAGCAAAAAAACAACUUUGUUGUUGAAAAAUGUAAAACAAAAAAAUAUUGAAGGUGGAGUGCUUUGACAAGACGGAAGAUCACUGUAGGUGAAGUUCUCCUGUGCUCCACAGCCACCCAGAGGAAUUCCAAAACCAGCAGUGGAGGACUUGGGGAGGACAGGAGGGAAAACAUGGCGAGUUCAUCAGCUCUGUUUCCUUUAUUAAAAUAUUUCUGUAAUUGGUGGUGGGAAAUUGAAGAAAUCAAGUGAUUGCAUCAGCGCUGGAAAAAGCUGCCAGCACUUGGCAGUGGAAGAGAAUAUAUGCUUUAUACUGGACUUUUUGAAAAAGAGGCUGAGUUUGGCCAGAUUGCCGACCAGCAAUGGAAAAACUAAUUAGGUGCCUUGCCUGUGAGCCAGACGCCCAGCAGGGCUGUGGCGCAUGGCUCCCGCCGCCUCUGAAGAGGACACUUUCUAGUGAAUUCAGUUCGUGCUACCCUUGAGCAGCCUGUGCUACAGCAGGCACAUUUGUGAAUCUCCCAGCCUGUGCCUGGCGUCGGAACUGUAGCUUCCCAAAGACUUACCUGCCCUGGGAGAUGGCGGGCAGCUGCUGGCCACAGCCCUGGGCCUGCACCUUUAUCUGCAAACUGGGAGAGCGGGGAUGGGAGUCAGUGGGUAGGAGGUGGGCAGAGGCCUGGGCCUCCCAGUGUUCGGGCUCCCACACUGCUGCCCUCACCCACUAUGUGCAUCUUCCCAACUUCUGGACAUCCUCACUCCUCCUCUGUCCAAUGUAAAUCAGAAUAGUGGGCCGGGCGCAGUGGCGCACGCCUGUAAUCCCAGCACUUUGUCAGGCUGAGGCAGAAGAAUCACUUGAGCCAGGAGUUGGAAACCAGCCUGGGCAAUACAGUGAGACCCUGAUUCUACAAAAAUAAAAAAUUAGCUGGGCGGGGUGGCGUGAGCCUAUAGUCCCAGCAACUCAGGAGGCUGAGGUGGGAGGAUUGCUUGAGUCCAGGAGGUCAAGGCUGCACUGAGCUAAGAUUGGGCCACUGCCCUCCAGCCUAGGCGACAGAGCAAUACCCUGUCUCAAAAGAAAAGAAGAAAAAGAAAAGCACCUAUCUCCAAGUUAGUGUGGGAAUUAAAUGAGAGGGGCACAUAGGACUUGGCACAUAAUAAGCUCUUAUUAAUAAUAGCUACUAUAAGUUAAUAAAAUAUCCGAUGGAUCUUUUAAAAAAAGCACUUUUCAGAAAUAAGGAAAAACCCCCACUCCACAAGCACCCGUUGUGAAAACCCUCCACCCUGGCACCCCACAGUGCCCACUGUGAAACUGGUACCAUUCAUUUUGAUUCAUGAGAAGACAGACUGUCCUUCUGAUUUGUAUUUCUUUGUUUCAUGGCCCAGAAUCAAAUGCCCAGCCCUCUGGGGGCCAUUCUCCUGUAGUGCCUGGGAUAUGCCCCAGCCUUGCCACUCAAAGCCCAGUCCCUAACCAGCAGUGUGGGCACCCCUGGGAGUCAGCUGGCAGUGCCAACGCUCCACCCCUCCCCGAGCUCCUAGAUGAGAAUCUGACAAAAGACCCCCAGUGAUUGUGUGUUCACCAGCCUCGCAUUCUCAUGCAUUUUAGCAUCCCUAGGAAUAGCCUGGAGGGGCUGACUUAGUGUCUGGGCCCCACCCAGGAGAUUCCAAUGCUGUGGCUAGAGAGGGGCCCAAGAGGGCAGAUUUCUAACCAACUCCUAGAUGGUGCCAGCACCGCUGGUCCCCAAACAUUUCAAGCAGCACCAUUCUUAAGGGGAAAAUUCCUUGGCCGCAGCUCGAACUUGCUGUGCCACCACUGUAAUGGGAUUGGGAGACCUGGCCAACAUGGUGGCCCAUUUCCUAGAUGUGCAGUGAAUAUCCAAGGAGGCAGAUUGGUCUGCAGAGAGGAGGAGGAUGCUGAGUGACAAACCUCCUGUAGUUCUGCACAACUCAAGCUCAUUUCUUCCUCACAUUACAUAUCCAUCCUGAGUUUUGACGGGGCUGUGUCACUCAAGGAUGAGUGACCGCUGGUAACUUCUACCACAGAGGGCAAGUCCAAGAUGCCCCAGCACCUUAGAGGUAGACCAGAGCCCAGGUCCUCAGCUCCUGUCCCGCAGUCCCCACUCCUUUCAGGCCCCUGGCUCCACCCACCUCAUCUGAGCCACUCUCCCCGCAGAGAGUCAGAAUGGCGGUCCUUCUCACCGUCUGCACACAUGACCUGAGGACCUCUGCAUCAGGCACUAGACUGACAUGGGCUCAAGGUAGGGAAAUUGACACGAAACAAACAUGGCAAAAAAUACCAAGUUCAGAUAUGAGGAUUGAGAUGGGAGAAGAGAGCCAGGCAAGGAGACAAGCCCCAUCGGGGGAGCCUGGGGGGCUUCCCUCAACACGCGAAGGAGAGGGGGAAAGGACAGAGGCCCGUGCUGAGGGGAGGACUCAGGGAGGACAGAGAUGGGCAUUUGAGGAGCUGAGGGACCCGAGGAAAGGAGGCAGACACCGGGUGCUGCAGGGUUUCACAUGGAGUUCACAGUUCGCAUUUCAUCCUGAGUGCAGGGAAAGCCAUGAGAGCGUUUUAGGGGAGUGACAUACUUGGGUUUCUAGUUGAACGAUGGCAAUCACUCAUGUUUUCUGACCAGCACACGCUUCUGCCCACUACUUCACCCUCACUGUCAUCCCCUGUGGUAGGCACUCUGUCAUUAUCCCCAUUUUCCAGAUGGGAAAACUGUAGCUAAUAAAGAUGAAGUGCCUCGCCCAAGGCGUCACUGCUAGAAGGGAUGGAGCCCACGCUCUUUCCCUCUUUGCUGCAGAAUGUUCCCUCUGAGCCGUGUUGAGACAGGCAAGAUGGGAAGAAGUAGAAGGAUUUGAGAUAGAUAACUUGGAACCACGAGGCUGCUUGGGUAUGAGGCAGGGGGAAGAGAGGCGACAGGGCAGGGCCCAGGUUUCUGGCUCAGGCCUCUGGGUCAAAGGCCAUUUAGCAAAAAUGCUGGAGGAGGUGCAGGUCUGGAAGACCACUUGAGAUGUUCCUGUAAUUUGCACGACGCCUUGCCUGGAGAGAGCACCUUGCAGUUAUCAGUACUGAGUUGUCUUGGAAUGCUUGGAGAACUCAAGUUCAGCCAGAGGAGGUCAAGUCCAGAGGUCAGCUGAGGAAGGGAGGAGGAGAUGGGCACAGAUCUGUCAGGCCAGGGAAGAUGAGCUCAAAUAAAGAUCAGGAAGCCAGGCCAGGUACCCAGGGAACAGCAGGCUGGGGAGGGUUUGGGGAACCUGGGAGUGCAGGGUCUUGUUGGUUUGGUUAGAGGCUCUAAACUCCAAAGGCCACAGGGCCCCUGAUGAGUGGAGUAGGCUGGAUCCAAGACCCUAGGGUGCUCAGGCAAACUGCACGUGUCACCGCUCCUCAGCUGCUGCAGCUGGUGGCCACGUGGCAGUGCCAGGGUCACACUCACAGAGAUGAGGAGAAGCUGGGCCCCCUUUGAUCUUCACAGUAGCCUAUGAGAUGGUCCCCAGAUCCUCCGAUGCUUCAAGAGGAGCUGGGCACCACAGUUAAGUGAAGUUUCCUAAAUUUUAAGUGUUGGUCAUUUGUGUUUAAAAAUGUGAAAACAAAAGAAAUAAAAGUGCAGCCAGACAAAGCCUCUCUGCCUGCACAUGGCUGCUGAAAGGCUGAAAUGGAUGGAGGUGGUCUCACCCAGGGGAUCCCAGGGACUGACGUUCCUAUCGCAGGGAAGGUGUCACACACGGAGCUACGGAACAGCAGGGCCGGAGCAAACAAAGCCAGCCCAGCUGCCUCGGCUAUUCCAACAGGGGCUACACUGGAGACAUUUUAAAAAUAAAGGGGGUGAGGGGAAAGAAUUCUCCAGAAACUUUGGUUCUUCUGUAAUGGCAAGUAUAAUUGCAAAAAACAUCUUGUCAGCCUGUAAAAUGACACUUUCACAGGUUUUCUUAGCAAGGGAGCUAGAUGGGCAAGAACCAAGCGUUCAAGUUCGGGGACCGUUCGAGCCCAGUUUGCUUUGCUGUGUUUCGUAGCCAUUAAUGUCCCCCCGCCAAUUACCACCAGUCAUUUUGCAAAGUUAUCAUUACUACUGUUUAAAAGAAAAAAAAACAUUGCUCAUUUUAGAAAGCUGUCUGUCAAAAAUGCUUAAAAUAAAAGCAGUCUUGGCAUUCGAA